UCAAGGAGUUUCAGUUUAUUGAGAAAAGCCAAGAAAAAAAGACAAAGCCAAGAAAAAAAAAUUCCGGGGCUAGGUCAAUCAGAGAAACUUUGCCUCUUCUCGAUUCCUUUGGUGACAUAUAGUCAGUGAUACAAUGGUAAAUGUUUAAUGACUGGAUAUCUGGGAGAAACACCUGGACUUCUAAGGUCUUCCAAUUUAUAUGGUAUAAGUAGUCCCUUUAUGGCUGAUUUCAAGGUGCCAAUAUUGUGUCCGGAAUUGGUGGGUUCUUGGUCUCACUGAUUUCAAGAAUGAAGCUGCGGACCCUCGCGGUGAGCGUUACAGCUCUUAAGGUGGCGCGUCUGGGGUCUGCCCCUUCUGAUGUUCAGAUGUGUUUGGAGUUUCUUCCUUCUGGUGGGUUUGUGGUCUCGCUGGGCUCAGGAAUGAAGCUGCAGAUCUUCACGGUGAGUGUUACAGCUCAUAAAAGCCACGUGGACCCAAAGAGUCAGCAGUAGCAAGAUUUAUUGCAAAGAGCGAAAGAACAAAGCUUCCACACUGUGGAAGGGGACCGGAGCGGGUUGCCACUGCUGGCUGGGGCAGCCUGCUUUUAUUCUCUUAUCUGGCCCCACCCACAUCCUGCUGAUUGGUAGAGCCCAGCGGCCUGUUUUGACAGGGCCGUGAUUGGUGCGUUUACAAUCCCUGAGCUAGAUACAAAAGUUCUCCACAUCCCCAUCAGAUUAGUUAGAUACAGAGUUUCCACACACAGGUUCUCCAAGGCCUCACCAGAGCAGCUAGAUAGAAUGUCUAUUGGUGCACUCACAAACCUUGAGCUAAACACAGGGUGCUGAUUGGUGGGUUUACAAACCUUGAGCUAGAUACAGAGUGCCGAUUGGUGUUUUUACAAUCCCUGAGCUAGACAUAAAGGUUCUCCAAGGCCCCACCAGAGCAGCUAGAUACAGAGUGUCGAUUGGUGCACUCAUAAACCUUGAGCUAAACACAGGGUGCUGAUUGGUGUGUUUACAAACCUUGAGCCAGAUACAGAGUGCUGAUUGGUGUAUUUACAAUCCCUGAGCUAGACAUAAAGACUCUCUAUGUCCCCACCAGACUCAGGAGCCCAACUGGCUUCACCUAGUGGAUCCCGCACCGGGGCUGCAGGUGGAGCUGCCUGCCAGUCCGGCGCCGUGCGCUCGUACUCCUCAGCCCUUGGGUGGUCGAUGGGACUGGGCGCCGUGGAGCAGGGGGUGGUGCUCGUCGGGGAUGCUCGGGCAGCACAGGAGCCCAUGGAGUGGAUGGGAGGCUCAGGCAUGGCGGGCUGCAGGUCCCGAGCCCUGCACCGCGGGAAGGCAGCUAAGGCCCGGCGAGAAAUCGAGCACAGCGCCGGUGGGCCGGCACUGCUAGGGGACCCAGUACACCCUCUGUAGCCGCUGGCCCGGGUGCCAAGUCCCUCACUGCCCGGGGCUGGCAGGGCCGGCCGGCUGCUCCGAGUGCAGGCCCGCCAAGCCCAUGCCCACCCGGAACUCCAGCUGGCCCGCUGUCACCUCUCAAUAUGACGCCACUAAACAUGGAGUUGAUAACAGGUGUGCAGUAGCUCAACAUUAUAUAGUAUUUCUACCAUACAGAUACAGUAGUAGACAGAGCUUGAUGAAUAUAGAACAAAUUUGCGUCAGACAAUAGCUUUUUGUUUUUAGAUAGUUUCUUUAAGGGUGAAAACAUUUAACCAGGCUCUCUUGAAGCCCUGCUGCCUGGGGGAAGUCAUUUGAUUUUUGCUAGUCUGUAUGCAUUGUUUAUGUACAGACUUUAUGGUUUUGUUCUCAAAGGCAUCUCCUCCUACCCCGAGCCUCACACUGCUGGGGUUUCGUUUGUUUUAAAUCUUGGUUGGAGGGGGCACUCUCUCCAGAAAGUAAAAGACAACGGAUCUGGCUCCAGUCCAGGACGGAAAGCAUAACGCUUGAUUUCUGGAUGGGGUUUGCACAAGGACAGCACGUGAGUUCUGCUCUCCGUGGGACUCAGACCGGAUAGGCCGUGAAAAUCUCUAAGGUGUCAGUCCACGCAACCUAACCUGGCAAAGGGAAUGCUUUGCAAACUCAGGCCCCAGAACAGAACUCGGCCUACCAGAUCCAGGGAGCCAAAGCACGCAGGCGCAGACAGAGUAGCGAAUCCAGAACCCUUGAUGUGUCCACAGAUGAAGAGGAUAAAAUACAUCACUCCUCAGAAAGUAAGGAUGAUCAGGGUUUGUCUUCUGACAGUUCUAGCUCUCUUGGAGAAAAAGAACUUUCAUCAACAGUUAAGAUCCCAGAUGCAGCUUUUAUUCAGGCAGCCCGCAGAAAACGUGAAUUGGCCAGGGCCCAAGAUGACUAUAUUUCUUUGGAUGUACAACAUACCUCCUCCAUCUCUGGUAUGAAGAGAGAGAGCGAAGAUGACCCUGAGAGUGAGCCUGAUGACCAUGAAAAGAGAAUACCAUUUACUCUAAGACCUCAAACACUUAGACAAAGGAUGGCUGAGGAAUCAAUAAGCAGAAAUGAAGAAACAAGUGAAGAAAGUCAGGAAGAUGAAAAGCAAGAUACUUGGGAACAACAGCAAAUGAGGAAAGCAGUUAAAAUCAUAGAGGAAAGAGACAUAGAUCUUUCCUGUGGCAAUGGAUCUUCAAAAGUGAAGAAAUUUGAUACUUCCAUUUCAUUUCCGCCAGUAAAUUUAGAAAUUAUAAAGAAGCAAUUAAAUACUAGAUUAACAUUACUACAGGAAACUCACCGCUCACACCUGAGGGAGUAUGAAAAAUACGUACAAGAUGUCAAAAGCUCAAAGAGUACCAUCCAGAACCUAGAGAGUUCAUCAAAUCAAGCUCUAAAUUGUAAAUUCUAUAAAAGCAUGAAAAUUUAUGUGGAAAAUUUAAUUGACUGCCUUAAUGAAAAGAUUAUCAACAUCCAAGAAAUAGAAUCAUCCAUGCAUGCACUCCUUUUAAAACAAGCUAUGACCUUUAUGAAACGCAGGCAAGAUGAAUUAAAACAUGAAUCAACGUAUUUACAACAGUUAUCACGCAAAGAUGAGACAUCCACAAGUGGAAACUUCUCAGUAGAUGAAAAAACUCAGUGGAUUUUAGAAGAGAUUGAAUCUCGAAGGACAAAAAGAAGACAAGCAAGGGUGCUUUCUGGGAAUUGUAACCAUCAGGAAGGAACAUCUAGUGAUGAUGAACUGCCUUCAGCAGAGAUGAUUGACUUCCAAAAAAGCCAAGGUGACAUUUUACAGAAACAGAAGAAAGUUUUUGAAGAAGUGCAAGAUGAUUUUUGUAACAUCCAGAAUAUUUUGUUGAAAUUUCAGCAAUGGCGAGAAAAGUUUCCUGACUCCUAUUAUGAAGCUUUCAUUAGUUUAUGCAUACCAAAGCUUUUAAAUCCCCUAAUACGAGUUCAGUUGAUUGAUUGGAAUCCUCUUAAGUUGGAAUCCACAGGUUUAAAAGAGAUGCCAUGGUUCAAAUCUGUAGAAGAAUUUAUGGAUAGCAGUGUGGAAGAUUCAAAGAAGGAAAGUAGUUCAGAUAAAAAAGUCUUGUCUGCAAUCAUCAACAAAACAAUUAUUCCCCGACUUACAGACUUUGUAGAAUUCCUUUGGGAUCCUUUGUCAACCUCACAGACAACAAGUUUAAUAACACAUUGCAGAGUGAUUCUUGAAGAACAUUCCACUUGUGAAAAUGAAGUUAGUAAAAGCAGACAGGAUUUACUUAAAUCCAUUGUUUCAAGAAUGAAAAAGGCAGUAGAAGAUGAUGUUUUUAUUCCUCUGUAUCCAAAGAGUGCUGUAGAAAACAAAACAUCACCUCAUUCAAAGUUCCAAGAAAGACAGUUCUGGUCAGGCCUAAAGCUCUUCCGCAAUAUUCUUCUUUGGAAUGGACUCCUUACAGAUGACACCUUGCAAGAACUAGGACUAGGGAAGCUGCUAAAUCGUUACCUUAUUAUAGCACUUCUCAAUGCCACACCUGGGCCAGAUGUGGUUAAAAAGUGCAACCAGGUAGCAGCAUGUCUACCAGAAAAAUGGUUUGAAAAUUCUGCCAUGAGGACAUCUAUUCCACAGCUAGAAAACUUCAUUCAGUUUUUAUUGCAGUCUGCACAUAAAUUAUCUAGAAGUGAAUUCAGGGAUGAAGUCGAAGAAAUAAUUCUUAUUUUGGUGAAAAUAAAAGCUUUGAAUCAAGCAGAAUCCUUCAUAGGAGAGCAUCACCUAGACCAUCUUAAAUCACUAAUUAAAGAAGAUUGAAUAAACUUUAUUGGAAAAUGCUAAAAUUUUAAUAUAGUUACACUCAGUUCCUUUGUUUGAGAAGAAGCUGGUGCCUCUCUCUUCUUUAUUCCCUGUAAUAGAAGGUAGGAUUUGAAAAAAAGCAGGACUCCACCUCUGUAUUCCCCCGUGCUUUACCUUCUGGCAUCAUGAAAAGCUGCCAUGAUUCUGUGGUGUUCUAAGGAAUUAAAUGCACUGGAGCUUUAAGAGCUCAACGUGUUUCCCUUUGAUUCUUUUGGCUGGUCUUUCAAUUUUCUUAAGAGGGGAACUGGAGAAACCUUGCUAAAGGUUUUAGCUUAAGUGAGCAUGCUACUAAGUCUUCUGUCCUGAACCACAAUAAUAUCUUUUAGUUCUCUUUAACUACCUUUAUUUAAAAAUAAGUCAAUAUGAAAAUCUCAGUUGGAGUGAAUUAUUUGCUAAGUAUUAAAUGAUUAAGGCAUGUGCCGAUUGUCAAAUUAUCCUUCAGAAAUCUGUACCAAUUUAAUGUACCAACAUAAGCAUAAGUGAGUGCCAAUGAAUCCCUACCAGCAGUAGUUAUUAUCCUUUUUAAAAAUGCAUUGAAAAUUUGAAAGGUAAAAAUCUUAUUUUAAUAGCGUAUUUUGUGUUGGCUAUUAGAGAGUAAACAUAUUGGUUUUGGCCAUUUGUAAUUAUUUCUGAAAUAUCCAUCUUUUUCUUAUGGACUUUAAGACCUUUAUAUUUUUAAAGAUAUUGAUUUUUUGCCCAUGCUUGUGGCAGAAGUUUUCCUUAUUUGCCAUUUUUCUUUUAUUUUUUUUUUAAUUGUAUUUUUUGAGACAGGGUCUGGCUCUGUCACCCAGGCUGGAGAGUAGUGGCACAAUCUCGGCUCACUGCAACCUCUGCCUUCUGGGCUCAAGCAAUCCUCCCACUUCAACCUCCCAAGUAGCUGGGACUAUAGGCAUGCGCCACCAUGCCCAGCUGAUUUUUGUAAUUUUUUGUAGAGAUGGGGUUUCGUGACAUUGCCCAGGCUGGUCUCGAACUCUUGAGCUCAAGCAGUCUACCCACCUUGACCUCCCAAAGUGCUGGGAUUACAGGCUUGAGCAACCAUGUUUGGCCUUUCUUUUAAAUUUGUUGAUGUUUUUUGAAGCAUUAAGUCAUUACUUAUUAGCAAGUUACUAUUUUGUUUUUUUGUCAUUGGUGGUAGGACUAAGAAGGAAACAGAUAUUUUAAAUACUCACAACAUGUGAUUCAUUUUCUGAUAAAAUAUUUGUCUAAUAAAACAGAGGCAAGAUAAUUUAAUCAAAAGAAAUUAAGAAAAUUUUCCAAAAAUGUUAGUUUACUAGUAAUUUUUCUAAGUCUACUUAUUAAAUAACUUAAGGGAAACUGUAAAUAUAUUUUGCAAAUUGUUGUUCAAAAGAUAAUUGGAAAAAAUUGAAUAUAUUGUAGGAUUUGAAUAUACAGCCUACUUUUAUGUCACCUCUACCUUCAAAACUACAUAUAAUUUAUUUUAGGAGUUGGAUUUGUUAUGUCUGUUGCAGUGAGGACUUGUGAUUCACUGGUAUGAAGAAUUUUUUGAUGUUUAUAUUAGUAACAAAAUUAUACAAGGAUAGAAUCUCAUCUAGAAAAUGCAAACUAUUGUUGAAAAGCAGUUAGCAUUUCCACACAACCGCUGUCCCCAGAGAUAACUGCUGUUUUCAUUUUAAUGUUAUCCUUUUAGACCUUUUCUCUAUUUACAAAAAUGUUACGUGUUUCUAUGUGUACAUAGUUUUGGGUUUUUUUUUUUUUUUUACGUAAGUGGCAGACACUUUAUUGCACAUGAAAUUUGUAAUUUUUUUCUAUUUAAGUACACAUUUGGAAAUUAUCCUCUGACUUUUGGAUUUUUAACUAAAUAUGUUGGACGUGUUCCUUUAUAUAUUUAAGUUCAGCACAGAAACUUUCCUACCUUUUUGUGGAAGAUAAAAUAUUAAAACUGCUUUCAAAACUACAAA